CUUUCAGUUCUGCUUGCUGUCGGCACCGCUGCGUUACCCGGAACCGCCGGGCCGAACAGCAUGACGUCCGCUUUGGAGAACUACAUCAACCGAACUGUUGCCGUUAUUACAUCAGAUGGGAGAAUGAUUGUGGGAACACUGAAAGGUUUUGACCAGACCAUUAAUUUGAUUUUGGAUGAAAGCCAUGAACGAGUAUUCAGCUCUUCACAGGGGGUAGAACAAGUGGUACUAGGAUUAUACAUUGUAAGAGGUGACAACGUUGCAGUCAUUGGAGAAAUCGAUGAAGAAACAGAUUCUGCGCUUGAUUUGGGGAAUAUUCGAGCAGAACCUUUAAAUUCUGUAGCACACUGAGGAAAAACUACAUACUUGGACAUCUGUAAAUCUUUGUACAGAAACUGAUUAUUCUGAGGAUGAUAUAUGGAGUUUUUAUGAGUGUGUCACUGGAUUUUGACUCCUUAUUGAUUCAUUGUAAUAUGUAAAUUAAAAUAUUUCUACAUUUUAUUGAAAAAAAAACCUUUUUUUUUGCCUAAAUAUAAGUUUGGUAGCUUGGUUUCUUUUUUUUAUUAAAUAGUGUGAAAAUAUAAUGGGCAUUUUGAAAACUUUUAGAAAAAAGUAGUACUUUUUGAUACUUUAGUAUUUAUGGAAACUAGUGGAAAAGAGAAAUUAGUGUGCUAUAUAAAUCAGGCAUUCAAGUAACAGUAAUACAGGAUAUAUGUGUUUUCUUUCCCUGAUGUUUAGGAAAAUCACAGGAGGGUAAAUCUUUGCUGGAGUUAUCUGAAUCAUUGGCAUUUAUCCGAUUCCACUGGUGGUAGUUUGCUAGUGCUUCUAAAAGUUGCUCCCUAGCACUGAGAGGUGUGGGUAGGUAAAAAUGUGUUUGCUUGAGAAAAGCAAAAAUGCUAACAAGGUUUUGAUAGAUUGGCCCAAAAUUCUAACUUGAAUAUUAAGAAUGACUAGGAAUGGUAGAAUUGACAGAGAUGAUUAGUAAAGUCUCUUGAUGCCCAAUUGGUUAGGUAUGAAAGUAAUAUGAACACAUUAAUGUUGAAUUUUACAGACAGUAUAUUUGAAAAAAAUUGAUUCCAUGUAGUCUUCAAUUUUUAAUUUUUAAGAAUUGGAGAAUUUCUAAUGUUAAAGUUAGUUUAUAAAUGUGAGUAAAUAAACUCUAAGUUUGUAUUGAAGUAGUGCUAGCUAUUAUUGUCAGCAAUUUUCCAUGAUUCAUUAUCCAUAAACCUGAUUUCAGAAGACGUCAACUCAGUUUUUUAAAUAAUUGAAAGAAACAAUGUAAGUAGUGUUUAGAUAUUCAGGCUAGUCCAUAAAAUUUCUGAUCAACUCAUGUAUAGGCCCAAGUGUGUGUCUUUGUGAUGAGAAGAACAUAGAAAAAUAUUUACAUCCUUGUAAUUGAAACAAAUUUAAAUAGUUUAUUUGUUUUGUUUUUAUGAAAGUGCUUAAAAAUAGUAGUUGGCAAGCUUUUUCUAUGAAGAUCCAGAUAGUCUUUUAGGCUUUGAAGGCCAUGUGGUCUGUCACAGCUACUCACCUCUGCUAUUGUGGCCUACAAAUAACCAUAGAUAAUACAUAAAUGAAUAGUGGCUGUCUUCCAGUAAAACUUCAUUUAUAAAAAUGGAGGUGGGGGUUGGAUUGGGCUUGAAGGCAUAGUUGCUGACCCUUGGCUUAAUACAAGUUCAAUAAGAAAAAAUGAACAAUUUGUAUAAAUUCUGGAAUAGAUCCUUAUAGAGAGUUUAGAGGUGGGUUUCAUUCAUAUUUUAAAAUAUUUUAAACUUCAUACUUAUUAAACAUAAUAGCUUUUUGGGGGAGGAAAAUAUCUUCACUCAAAUCAGCCUUAUAAGGGGAGAAGCACUAUUCUCUAGAAUUAUUUGGUUGAUGUUAAGGGCUGUCUCUGGGAGAAUUAGAGAAGUUAGCUAGUAUUGGCUAUUCAUAAGUACUUGACUUGUAGUAUAAUGUUUUAUAAUCAAUUUAUUAAUAAAAUGAUGGAAAGUGGGUAAGGCAAACAGGCAAAUUUAGGGACUGUGAAUGAAAUAUUGUAGUAUAUGGCAUUUUGAAUUGGUAAAGUAAUUCCAAAAAUUAAAUAAGAAUACACAUUGUUCAGUUGCUAAGAAAAAUGCAUUCUAACAGUACAAAUGAAGUCCAGAGUCAGAUCUUUUCUCAAAAUACUUGGCAUAUCAACACAUUACACAUAAACAAAUAAAAACCAGUCCUGUCCCUCAUGAUAAUGGGUUUCUAAUGUGAUGUAUUCUUGCAAUCUGAAACACCUUAUAAAGCUGUAUUUUCCUGAUUGAUGUUGGAAAAAGCAUUCCCAAAAUGUGAAUUAUUGUUUUUAUGAAUAGUUACAGAGGAUGUGAUGACAAUAUGCCAGAUAAUCUAUGUAAUUCUUUAUUCCUGGAUACAAGCACAUGGUGGACUGUUUUCUCACAACCGAUUAAAAUUGGAUUUAUUUUUGCAUGAGAAUUGUAAGGGAGCCACAACCAUGAGUAGUAACAUAAUUAAUAUACAGUGUCAAUAUUUUAUAUUUAAUGAGACAUUUAUUCUAUAAUCAGUUCUUAUUUAUAAAGAGGCGCAAAUCAAUUUCAACCUGUAAUUACCUCUGUGCUUUGUGACUCAGGCACAAUCUAAACCCAGCUUAAUGAAUCAAAGAGAUGUUUCUUGGCAAGAUAUUUUCAUUAAAGUUAUUUGGAAAGGGCAAUUAACUGCAAAAGGGACUUUUUUUUUUUUAACUGACAAGAUACUAUCUAAACUAAUAGUUUAAAAUAACAUUGCUUUUAUGUCAAAGCACUUUGGUAACUUGGCCUCACAUGCUGACAGUUUUGGCUAAAUAUUACAAAUCUUGAUCCCAGAAGAGCAAGAGAGAAAGUUUUACUAAUAUUUGCUUAAACAUCCUGUUUAACAACUUUAUAACAUCCUUCGGAAUUUUUAAGGUAAUAAUGUGAGAUAUAAGUAUGAUAAAAACAACUUUUAAAUGGUAUUUAAUGCAAAUACAGAAUAACGAUGUCAACAUUUUCCUCAGCCGUGUAACCUGAGAUUCAUCAUGGGAAUGAGAAAGUAAAGGCCCUUUGUAAUGGCAUGUGAACCAGACAAUUUAGUAGCCAGGGUUGUAAGGCAACUCUUAACUGACAAUAUAGUUAGUAUAUUCUGGGCCUUCAUCUUCAAAAUUAGUAGGUAGUAUUUAUUGAGUGCAUAUCAUGUGCCAGGCCUGGUGCUGAGUGCUUACAAUGAUCAUUUUAUAUAUGGGAAAAUUGAGGCUCAGCAGGGUCAAGUGACUUGUAAGAGGUAGCACUAGUAAGUAACAGUGCUCAAAUUCAACUAGGUCUUUCAGCUUUUUAUACAAUACUGCCUGUUAUCAGAAAGUAUAGUCUUAAAAUCUGCUAUCAAGCAUCUAUCAGAAGCCUGAUGAGAAAUAUUCAGAUGAUCUAACGCAGUUCCCAAACCUGCAUUGUGGGCCGUUUUCAUUACAAUUACCUAAGGUGCUUUAAAAAUUUUCUUGGGCCCUACUCGUUGUGGUUCAGCAGCUGUGUAAUGGAGCAAAAAGGAAUAGUCACUAAACAGCGAAGGAAAGUGGUGGAAUUAUUAAAAGACCUAGCACUUACCUGCUGGGAUGAGUCUCUAACCCCACAGAAUUGAUUUCAAACACAGGAUCUUAUUCAAGAUAAGGAUAAUAACAGCUAUCUUCUUGGGUUGUAAAAAGUAGCAUUAGACUGCAUUUUAAACAUUUGGUAUGAUUUUGAGGACAUAACCGUAAACAGCUAUUUAAUACUAUUCCAGGUAGUCAAAGGCCAAUGUAUAAAAGUUAAAAAUAUAGGUCUUGUCAGCUUUUUAAGCGUCUGUCCCACUGACUACCAUAUCUCUACAAGAGAAUAGAUGAGGAAUUGAGGUUAUGUGGGAAGUACGUGUAAGUUUACAGUAUUAAGAAAUGUACAAUAAAAUUUGUUUCUAUGUCAGCGAAUAUUCUUGACUCAAGGAGUUUGAAAGUGUAAACUCAAAGGUCUUUCACAUGUAAAGAGGAACCUCUCCAUUCUGUACUUGUAUAGUCAUUACCUCAUAUAGAUUUAAUUUUAUUAAAUUAAAUUUUACUUAUUUUGGGUUUAAAAAAACUUGGGCUGUGAAUCUCAGUUUUAAGUCAUGGGCAAAUUUGAUAAAAAUUCCUUUCUGUCUACAUGUAAUACUGAAAAAAAUGUUGAUAAGGUAAAGCUAUCUCCAUUUAGAUUGAUACCCAUUAAAUAGCAUAGUGCUCCCAUUAAACUAGCGACAAAUUCAUUUAAUUGUGAGAUAUCUAGUACUUAUGCUCCAUCCUGUUUAUAGGGAUUAUUGAUGUGAGAUUUGGUCAGAUGCUUUGAUGUGAUCUUCAUUCCUCUGUAUAGUGGGAAACCAUGAGACGUGCUUAGUCUUCAUAAAUCGAUGCUGCCUCCUAGUGGCCAUUGCUUUCUUUUCUACCUGUCCACAAACUUCAAAAAAAUAGAUUUUGGAAUUUUGUCAGGGACACUUAUCAAGCCAUUAAUACAUGCCAGGCAGUAUGCUCAAAGCUGUGGAUAGGCCAGGGAACAGUAUUCUUGUGCUUGUGAAGCUUCUAUCUGUCUGUAUCUACCUCAACCAAAUCAUCUUGACUCAGAUUUACUGUCGAAGGUCGUGUUAUUUCAUCAGAUUCUUUCAGUAUUCUGGGAUAUAAUUUAUGGGUUCUGGAUUCAUUCAAAACAACUAGAAACAGUCUUUUUAAAAUAAAUAUAAUUCAAGUCAAUUAUUUUCCCCAUCUAUUUUUUUUCUUUUAAGAUUGCUAAGUCUGUAGGUUGCAUAAUUCUAAGGAUAAAGGCGAAAUAGGACUUCACCAGGAGAAUUUCUUUCAUUAGUUAACAGUAUGCCAUCUCCUACUUACUGGCAUCAUCUGGGGAAUGAAGGAGCUGAGAAUUGUUCUUCCAGAUACCUUUCCGACCUCUUCUUGGUUUUGGCAUUAAGUUUUUUUUUAACUCAAUUUUUGUGUUAGUUUUUUGUUAUGCCUUUUCAUUUCCUUCUUUUUUUAAUGUUUCUUUUUUUUUAAGUCCUUUAAUUUUUAUUUAUUUAUUUAUUUAUUUAUUUAUUUAUUUAUUUAUUUAUUUUUGAGACACUUCUUGCUCUUUCGCCAGGCUGGAGUGCAGUGGUGCAAUCUUGGCUCACUACAACCUCCGCAUCCUGGGUUCAAGCGAUUCCCCUGCCUUAGCCUCCCGAGUAGCUGGGACUACAGGCACGCGCCACCACACCUGGCUAAUUUUUUUGUUUUAGUAGAGACGGGGUUUCACCAUGUUGGCCAGGAUGGUCUUGAUCUCCUGACCUCGUGAUCUGCCCACUUCGGCGUCCCAAAGUGCUGGAAUUACAGGCAUGAACCACCACGCCCAGCCUAAGUCCUUUUAUUUUACAGAGUAUUACUUGUUAGAAAUGGCACAGAUCAAGCAUUGCUACAACUGGUAUCAAAUUCCCAUCAAUGUCCCUACAAGGAUAUGAUACGCUUUCUCUCUUCUCUUUAGGGUAAUGUUCAAUUACACUGCAUAUAUUUUGCUAUUAUGUAGGUUUUUUUUUUUUUUCCACAUAUACUGGCUUUACAAAUGCCAUAUAAUUAGUAUGGUACCAAAUUGUUAUUACAUUUGAAAUACGUUAAAAAGAAUCCAGGAGUCAGGGUGGGUGGGGAGACAACUCCAGGGACACAAUACAUUGUGUCUUGUAUUAAAAACUAGUGUGUGUUGGGGUGGGGAACAGGCAGGAAACUAAUAUGUUUCUGUUUGAUAUAUGAAAAUAUGCACAAGCUAUCAUGUUUCAUCUCAUAUCAACAAAAUGAUUAUAAUAAAUCAUACUCUAGAAAACUCAUUAACUGAUACAAGUUGCCAGAAAAUGCUGCACUAUGGCUUAUUUCACAUUUUAAAAUAAAUGCCCUGAAAGUGAUCACAAUGAUAGUUAAAAGUUAAAUUUUUUAUUUUAAAAUUUAAAUUUUUAUUUUAAAAAAUAGCUCUCUGAAUCUGACUUGGAUAAGCUUUAUUUUAAUUGUGAUUCUGCUAAUUACAGAGACACUUCAAUUCACACUCAUAGGAGGUAUGAUUUUUAAAAGGAAAUUGUUGAUUAGGGUCUUGGGCUAGUCCAGUGUAGCAUGGCAGUGAAAGGCACAGACUCUGGAGUCAUACUUAGUUUGCAGAGCUUAGCAUAUUAAUCUUACCAUGUCUUAGUUGCUAUGAAAAUGAGUACCUGCUUCCUUGUACUGUCAAGAUUAAGAUAAGCAGUUAGCACUCCCUAGAACAUACUAAUUUGUCAAUAUUAAUGAUAGCUAACAAUUAUCCUGAUAUUGAAUGAUGGACUCCAAAUUAUUUAUUGUGGCCUAGGAAAAGUACUAAGAAGUAAUUGAUAGCAUUCCCUGAUAAUUUUGGUGAAAAGAAAAACUAUGAAAAUUCUGGACAGGACUGGAAAUUUAUUGUAAAUGAAAGUAUGCUUCCCUGGUGCAAAGGUAAUGUGAUGUUUUUAAUCACAUAUUUUAAAAUUAAAAAUUUGAUCAAAUUUUUAAAAGUAACACGAGGCAGAGAAAGUACAGAAAGGAGCAACCAGAGUCAAAGUGAUUAAGUUAUAAAAAGGUUAGAUUUCUUUGGUGUGAAAAGAUAAAUGAGAAAUGAGAAUAUGCCAGAGAUCUGAAAUGAAGAAUGGAUAAGAGCUUGCAUAUUUAAUUUUGUAUAUUAAAACCAAAUAUUCUAUGAAGAUUGGAAGGAUAAUUUUAGGUCAAAUGAAAUUCUACAUUAAAGAAAGAAGAAUAAACCUUAACAACUCAUUAGUAAUCCUUCAUUUCCUGAGUAUUUACUGCAUGACAGUAACAGAGAUGACAUGCCCGGUAAACUGGUGUUUGAAGGCAAUAUAUAAAAGCUUCCCAUGCAUGGCAAAGAUGCAUUUUCCUCUAUGCAUAGCAAUAUGGGAGAGAUUGGAGGAGAAUCUUCAUGGAAAUGGAUGACUUGUGCUUGACCCUAAGGAUAGUAAGGAUUUCCAUAGAUGGUUAGGAAAACUUCAAAUUGGCAGACAGGAAGGCAAGAAGGAGUAAGAUGUGGUUGAGUAAUAAGGAGUAGACUGACCUCUCUGUACAGUAAAGGCUCAAAUCCUUUUUAUUGCAAAGAAAGGACCUGUCCUUCACCAGUUCCUGGAAGAAAAUCUCUUGAGUCCUUGGGAUGUCUUACCUGUUAAGAGUGCUUUUGUAUGCCUGAGACCAUAGGCCUUGCUGUUACAGUUUAAGCUCUGGGAAACGAGAUUCAGGAGCUAAGGUCAGUUAUGAGGGAACUGAAUAUUUAUGUGACUGAACCCUCAUAAAAACCCUGAACACCAAGGCUCAAGAGAGCUUAUUAGCAAUACUUUGCAUGUGUUGGUAAACACCGUUGCUGAACUAGGUGCUGUCUGUGCAGCUCCACUGGGAGAGGACAUCUUGAAGUUUGUGCCUGGUUUCUCCUGAUUUUCACCCUGCACACCUUUUCCAUUUACUGAUUUUAAUCUAUAUCCUCUCACUAUAAUCUGCAACUGGGAGCAUAGCAGCUUUUCUGAGUCCUAUGAUUCCAAGUGUAUCAAUGAACCUCAGUAUGAUCUUGGGGACCCCCAACUCACUAUCUAAAUAAAAUUUUCAUUGAAAAUUAGUGAGAAGGGAAGAGAUGGCCUUCAAUACUAGUGCAAAGUUAAUACUUUAUUCUUAGAGCAGCAAGUUGAUUUUAGGGGAUUAAAAAUCUAAGACGUUUAAGGGAACAUGAAUUUGGAUGCAUUGAACAGAAUUGGUAACCUGAAGGAGAAACUGGAGGCAAAUUGUUUCAAGUUAGGAAGCUAUUGCAGUAAUUAAACUGAGCUGACACAUUUUCAUGUCAGAUUUUCAGAUAUGAUAAAGGCUGGAAGUACAGAGUUUCAAAAGAUGUACAUAAAUUUAUGGAAAGGAAAUUUUGGAAUGGUGAUUCUAACCUUUAAGGUUGGUGCCAUGGAAGGAAAACAAGUAACUUUGCAACAAUCUGUUCAACAAUGAGAGUUACCAAAUGCCAGACACUGCUAAGUGCUGGGAACUUAGAUGUAACCAAAGACUUAAAAGAUACUAGUCUUUAAGACAGGCUUUGAGAAAUUCAAGUGUAGGGUAAGGCCACCUCCCCAGCAAGUAAAUACUGACAUGGUGAAGAUAUGUAUUGGGUGAUAUGAGAGCCCAUAGGAGAGACAUCUAAAGUUUAAUAGCAACACUAGGCUGGACUGAGUGGUGAAUACGUUGAUAUAGCAAUUUAAUAAAUGUGUUAUUGUCAAUGUAGGCAUUUUGCUCAUAGCUUAGGGCAAGUGAUAAAAAACAGAGCUUAACAAAGGACUGGAUGUUUUAGUUUGACAGCAGUGUCUAAAUUACAGAUUAGAGAACUAAUGACUAGCCAUACCGAAGACAUUUAUCUGGAAAUGCCUUCCCUAAGUGCCAACAGAGAAUGAAAAUAUAGUCAAUAGCUUUAAGUGACCCCAUGCAUCUUAAUGCCUUUCAAGCAACAUGUUUUUCUGACUUCCAAAUAUAAACAACCUAAGCAUUGUGCAGUAGCCAUGAGGGACUAGGUAUCCAAGUGCACAUUAUAUUGGCUUUGUAGAGCCAUUGGAGGGAGUAAUAGUUUCAGAGUCAUGAAACAAAUCAUAAGUAGCUGCUCUGGUGCUCUCUAGAGGCAGAACUUGCUGAAUUUGAAGACUAUUAAUGAUGCAGCUCUCACUGGUACAAGUGAAAAACCUCUCAGCCCUACACAGCAUCUUUAAGAAAGCUUUAAUUUUGGUUUUUCAGAGCAAUAUUCACAUGACAUCUUUCGGAUCUGGAAUCUUAAUUACCAUUAGGUUGGAACUCUACCUGAACUAAAAAUAAGUGGUCUCUAUCACGUUGAAAUUACUUUAAUAUUUUCAUUUAUGUUUAUACUAUUUAUUUAAAUGCGGAGAACAUGGCUAACCAUUCAGGACCAUUUAAUUAUCAAAUUAUUAAUGAUUCUUCCAUAAUAAACAAGCAAACUGUCAUACUUGUUGACUUAUAUUUCAUUCCAUGGAAUUCAAAUUUAAUUAAUUGAUAAAUCACAUUGUACUUUAUAAGAGUUUAUUCCUUAAGUGUUUGAAUUUACACUUUUUUCUCCUGUGACAGCAUCUAUUCCCAAGGCAAUCAACAUUUUAAUGGAACGAACUGAGGUUUGCAAUUGCUAAUGUUAUUCUCCCAUCCCAGUUUCUACUUGUUUCUUGUAAAAAAGGAGGUUUCUAAAUCUUGACUGUUGAUUGACAAUUAAUGGGCUAAAUUUCCCAUUAGCAAACACUUUUCACAUAUACACUAAUAUUAGUAUCUAAAUUAUAUUAAAAUCUAAUUUGGUAGCAAUUGACUUGAAAUUUGUGAUACUUCAACUUGUGCUAGGUUGUAGUUUUGCUUGUAUCACUCAUAGUUACUAAAAAUGCAAAAGGCAAAUUUGAAAUAACUAUAAAAAUAAACCUUUAAUGAACUUUUUAAUAUGCAAUACUCAAUUGUAAAUAACCAUUAUCUUUACUGAAUCAGAUGUUUCAUUAACUGUUAGCAGUUAUUUCGAGUUAUUUAUAUAUCACAGAAUUUUGAACUAAAGAUCAUCUAGCUGAAUUUCCUUUAUAUUAAAGAAGAGGAGAAAAUCUUAAUACUAAGUAUGUGUGAGCCUGGAGCUGCCAUGGAGCAUGUAGAGAGAGUCUCCUAGUUGAUACCAACUCAGGAAAGCAGAAUCAAGCAAUAAAGAGACAUUUUGGGCCUGAUGACAUCAUUUCAGCACCUGGAUCCAGCGAUGCCUAAAGAUGUGACUCCUAGACUUUUCACUUACAUGAGCCAAAACGGUUCCUUUGCAUCAAUAAAUCGCUCUGUGAUGCAUUUUAUAAUGUACAACCAAGAAUCUCAAUAUUUAUUAUUUUGCAUUAAAUAUCAGUAAGUUUGAUAUAAAAAGCUCAGUAAAAUUCAUUAAUUUGAGAAUGUGUCUAUAUCAUAGUAAAGUUUUAAACCUACAUAAUUUUCAAUAUUUAUACCUUUUACUGCAAAAAUAAAAAUGAGUUUAUCCUUGCCCUAAAGCUGUAAAAUUAAACUCUGUACAAUUCUAGUUAUUUGAAAUAUAAAAUAAAAUUAUUGGUCAUUUCAUGUAUACAUUUGUGGUAACACUUUAACUUUUUCCCUGUAAGGCCAUCUUUUGUAUGUUUCUGUUUCCAUCAAGCAGGCUUUUAAUGCAACUUUAUCUUCUGGGUUUCCCUAGUCAUAAUUAAGGGUUUGGCCCUAGUUCACAAGUAAUCUUCCAGCACAAAUUUUAUAAACAAAUGCCCUGUGAAUCUGCAUGGCAUAAAUCAAGUCUCUAGAUCCUGAUCACUUCUAUGUGAAUUUGUAAUAUUCUGCUUUUGGACUUGUAAGACCAAGAGCAGACUCCCUAAACACAGAGGAGGCAGUAAUUUAGGACAGCUUAAACAUUCUGGCUGACUGCCUCAUCAAUGCUAUUUAAUAACAGAAUUCUGGGGAUGUCUUGAAAUAGAUACAUUGGCAGUUUUUUUGUUUUUGUUUUUGCUUGUGUCACACAUAAUGCUGAUGAAGAAACCAUGAAGUGUCAUAUGAAAGGAAGUUACGAUUAUUAUUGGUGAGUACAUCAGUUAGAAUGGUAUUUGGCUAUAAGCACUGGAAACUCUGACUGCCAGUGGCUUUAACAGGCAGGAGGAGUUCAUUUAUCUCGAGAGAAAAGAACAGAAAAGUGAAAAGCAAGGCAGUUCAGACUGGGGCACCUACUCAAAGAAGUGACCCAGUACCCAGGCCACUAUUUUCUCUUUGCCAUCCUUUUGUUCUAAUAAUUUGCCUGUCAUCUCGUGACUCAUAUUUUCCAUCUAAUUAGAAUAAAGAAAGAUGAAAUAGGAAAGUGAGAUUAUCAUAUGGGAAAAAUAAAUGCUUUCCCAACUAUAACCAGCAGACUAUACUGGCAAAAUAUACUGCUUGAAUGCCAUUGGCCAGAUCUUUGUCAUAUGGUUACCCUAACUACAAGGGAGGCUAGGAAGGUGAGGGAUUUUUUUCCUUUUAUAGUGACAUUUUGCCACUCCAAAUAAAAAAAGGGUUGCUGUUAGGAAAAAGAGAAGAAUGGGGAUGGGGUGAACAACCAACAAUGCUGCCAUUGUGCUAGUAUAGAAGCAAGUAUCUCAGAGGCAGGUGAAAACAACUUCUAUGCCCAAACAGAAUUCUUUUUUAUCUCUGAUAUAAAAUGCAGAAUAUGAAUUUUAAUAAAUUCCCCAGGUGAGUCAUAUGCACAUUAAAGUUUGAGAAGCACUGAUCUAUACUGUCUUUCUACACACUUUUUUACCUUACUUUAUCCUUCAGGAUUCUGGCGUCAAGUCCCUCCCUAUCAGUCUUUAAAAACUGUAGCCUUAAAUCAGUAGGGAUAUAGAAGACAUGAACAAUACUUUCAUCCAUCUUGACCUAACUGCCAUUUAUAGAACGUUCUAUCCCAAGACAUCAGAAUAUAUAUUCUUUUUAAACAUUUAAUGAAAGGAUUUAACUCCCAAACUCCAAAGCAAGAUGUUCUAAGAAGACUCAUUUAAAAAAUUAAUCUCAAAAAACAGAUUUUAAAUUGUACAGGAGAAAUGCUUAUAUGAGAACAGAAUUAUGGGGCACUCUGAAUACUAAUUUAAGAAAGAAAUAUAAACCCCUUUUAAAACUCACAUAAUUUUCCCAUUUCCCUUGAAGAAGAUACUAAUAUUUCUGAUAUCAUAUAGGAGUAAAAAUUGCGGGGAGGUCCUAAUAUCCAAUAUUAAUAGAGCUGUGAUUAUUCAAGCUGUAGACUUAAAUUUUUUAAAUAGAGUAAUGGUUGUUUAGUAGAGAUUAAUAUCUAAAUAAGGAAAAUGAAGAAAGGGACUAAAAAUCAAGUAAAUAGGAUAAUUGAGUUUCAAUGGGCAAGAAUUUUUAUAUCAUGAUUUUACCACUCUGAAUAUCAAAGUCAGUGAUGUCUCCAAAAGGCAAAGGGAAGUGUACCAAUUUUUGGAGCACUAUAAAAAGUGAAAAGUCAUCUGCCAGAUCUAACAUGGUAUACUCUAAUGGAAAAAUCAUCAAGAUUCUCUUCCUUUUUAUGAUUCUAUAGUAACAGUUUAGUUGAGAAAAUAAAUCAUAAUUUGUGAUUUCAAACAUUUAAUAUGUGCACAUGUAUAUUAUAAUAUACUCAUCCUUUAUAUUUAUCAUGCUUUUUUGAAUAAAUUUGCCACCUUAUUGCAUAUGAAGAAUAUCUCCAUAUUCUUACAGCUGUUUUUCUUGGUUGCUUUCUAAUUCCUUUCCUCCCUUAUUGGUUACCUAUGAAUUGCUCAGUUCUAACAAUGAUUUGUAAAUUUUAAUACUAUAGAUAUAUUGCUGUUAAUUAUUACACCUAAAAAUAAAUUAUUUUACAGAGGCUA